AUUUGGAGAGUUAAAACUGUGCCUAACAGAGGUGUCCUCUGACUUUUCUUCUGCAAGCUCCAUGUUUUCACAUCUUCCCUUUGACUGUGUCCUGCUGCUGCUGCUGCUACUACUUACAAGGUCCUCAGAAGUGGAAUACAGAGCGGAGGUCGGUCAGAAUGCCUAUCUGCCCUGCUUCUACACCCCAGCCGCCCCAGGGAACCUCGUGCCCGUCUGCUGGGGCAAAGGAGCCUGUCCUGUGUUUGAAUGUGGCAACGUGGUGCUCAGGACUGAUGAAAGGGAUGUGAAUUAUUGGACAUCCAGAUACUGGCUAAAUGGGGAUUUCCGCAAAGGAGAUGUGUCCCUGACCAUAGAGAAUGUGACUCUAGCAGACAGUGGGAUCUACUGCUGCCGGAUCCAAAUCCCAGGCAUAAUGAAUGAUGAAAAAUUUAACCUGAAGUUGGUCAUCAAACCAGCCAAGGUCACCCCUGCACCGACUCGGCAGAGAGACUUCACUGCAGCCUUUCCAAGGAUGCUUACCACCAGGGGACAUGGCCCAGCAGAGACACAGACACUGGGGAGCCUCCCUGAUAUAAAUCUAACACAAAUAUCCACAUUGGCCAAUGAGUUACGGGACUCUAGAUUGGCCAAUGACUUACGGGACUCUGGAGCAACCAUCAGAAUAGGCAUCUACAUCGGAGCAGGGAUCUGUGCUGGGCUGGCUCUGGCUCUUAUCUUCGGCGCUUUAAUUUUCAAAUGGUAUUCUCAUAGCAAAGAGAAGAUACAGAAUUUAAGCCUCAUCUCUUUGGCCAACCUCCCUCCCUCAGGAUUGGCAAAUGCAGUAGCAGAGGGAAUUCGCUCAGAAGAAAACAUCUAUACCAUUGAAGAGAACGUAUAUGAAGUGGAGGAGCCCAAUGAGUAUUAUUGCUAUGUCAGCAGCAGGCAGCAACCCUCACAACCUUUGGGUUGUCGCUUUGCAAUGCCAUAGAUCCAACCACCUUAUUUUUGAGCUUGGUGUUUUGUCUUUUUCAGAAACUAUGAGCUGUGUCACCUGACUGGUUUUGGAGGUUCUGUCCACUGCUAUGGAGCAGAGUUUUCCCAUUUUCAGAAGAUAAUGACUCACAUGGGAAUUGAACUGGGACCUGCACUGAACUUAAACAGGCAUGUCAUUGCCUCUGUAUUUAAGCCAACAGAGUUACCCAACCCAGAGACUGUUAAUCAUGGAUGUUAGAGCUCAAACGGGCUUUUAUAUACACUAGGAAUUCUUGACGUGGGGUCUCUGGAGCUCCAGGAAAUUCGGGCACAUCAUAUGUCCAUGAAACUUCAGAUAAACUAGGGAAAACUGGGUGCUGAGGUGAAAGCAUAACUUUUUUGGCACAGAAAGUCUAAAGGGGCCACUGAUUUUCAAAGAGAUCUGUGAUCCCUUUUUGUUUUUUGUUUUUGAGAUGGAGUCUUGCUCUGUUGCCCAGGCUGGAGUGCAAUGGCACAAUCUCGGCUCACUGCAAGCUCCGCCUCCUGGGUUCAAGCGAUUCUCCUGCCUCAGCCUCCUGAGUGGCUGGGAUUACAGGCAUGCACCACCAUGCCCAGCUAAUUUGUUGUAUUUUUAGUAGAGACAGGGUUUCACCAUGUUGGCCAGUGUGGUCUCAAACUCCUGACCUCAUGAUUUGCCUGCCUCGGCCUCCCAAAGCACUGGGAUUACAGGCGUGAGCCACCACAUCCAGCCAGUGAUCCUUAAAAGAUUAAGAGAUGACUGGACCAGGUCUACCUUGAUCUUGAAGAUUCCCUUGGAAUGUUGAGAUUUAGGCUUAUUUGAGCACUGCCUGCCCAACUGUCAGUGCCAGUGCAUAGCCCUUCUUUUGUCUCCCUUAUGAAGACUGCCCUGCAGGGCUGAGAUGUGGCAGGAGCUCCCAGGGAAAAACGAAGUGCAUUUGAUUGGUGUGUAUUGGCCAAGUUUUGCUUGUUGUGUGCUUGAAAGAAAAUAUCUCUGACCAACUUCUGUAUUCGUGGACCAAACUGAAGCUAUAUUUUUCACAGAAGAAGAAGCAGUGACGGGGACACAAAUUCUGUUGCCUGGUGGAAAGAAGGCAAAGGCCUUCAGCAAUCUAUAUUACCAGCGCUGGAUCCUUUGACAGAGAGUGGUCCCUAAACUUAAAUUUCAAGACGGUAUAGGCUUGAUCUGUCUUGCUUAUUGUUGCCCCCUGCGCCUAGCACAAUUCUGACACACAAUUGGAACUUACUAAAAAUUUUUUUUUACUGUU